AGUGGAAACACUGCCCUCUCCCUUCUUGACCCCUAGCCCUUCCUUCCCUCCCUCCUUCCCUCCUGUCGCCGUCUCUUCUGGCGCCGCUGCUCCCGGAGGAGCUCCCGGCACGGCGAUGGGUUCUCGGGCCUCCACGUUACUGCGGGACGAAGAGCUCGAGGAGAUCAAGAAGGAGACCGGCUUUUCCCACAGUCAAAUCACUCGCCUCUACAGCCGGUUCACCAGCCUGGACAAAGGAGAGAAUGGGACUCUCAGCCGGGAAGAUUUCCAGAGGAUUCCAGAACUUGCCAUCAACCCACUGGGGGACCGGAUCAUCAAUGCCUUCUUUCCAGAGGGAGAGGACCAGGUAAACUUCCGUGGAUUCAUGCGAACUUUGGCUCAUUUCCGCCCCAUUGAGGAUAAUGAAAAGAGCAAAGAUGUGAAUGGACCCGAACCACUCAACAGCCGAAGCAACAAACUGCACUUAGAGGAAGAGAGAUAUAUAUAGAGAGAGAUCGAGACUGAAAUUGAGCAACACUCCUCCCAAGCAUGGAAUGUAAGUCCUUCCCCUCACUUUGAUAAGUCAGUUCAGGUCAGGAGAGUGCGAGUGCCGAGGAGAUUAGGCUAAUGAGAUUCCCCUCCUGAUGCUGUGAUUGGGGUUCUGCUAAGGAAAAAGGUUGGAAUGCCACAGAAAUGGCAGACUUCAGGAUGAGAUAGAAUAAUAACAAAGUGCUAUGCAGGUUAUGCUUGGUUUUAUUUUGUUUUUGCUUAAUUUUUUGAGAUAGGGUCUCACUCUGUCACCCAGGCUGAGUGCAGUGGCGUGAUCACAGCUCACUAUGGCCUUGACUUUCCUGGCUCAAGUGAUCUUUUUGCCUCAGCCUCUCAAGUUGCUGGGACCACAGGCGUGUGCACUACACCCAGCUAAUUUUUUAUUUUCUAAUUUUUUGUAGGGACAGGGUCUCACUAUGUUGCCCAGACUGGUCUCGAAAUCUUGGACGCAAGCAGUCAUCCCACCUUGGCCUCCCAAAGUGCUGGGAUUACAGGCAUGAGCCUCCAUACCCAGCCUGUUUUUUUCAUUACAUACUUUAGUCUUGGCUGUUGGAUUAACUUUUAUAGGAAGCUAAAAAUUAAUUAGAAUUCUGUUGCAGUCUAUGUAUAGGGAUCACAUUCAUGUAAUUAGACCAGUAAAACCGAAGCUAUUCUAAUGCCAAAGAAAAGACUAGAAGAGUCCGAGAAGUCCUCAAUUUCUGUCUAAAUGUGUUGCUUCUCUUUGAAGUUCCCACAGGGCUGUAUAAGCUGUAGCAUGGUGCCUCUUACUGUAGACUGAGAGCAAUUGAAUGUCAUAUACCUAGCAAUACAUUUGCCACUGAGACACAUUUACCUUAGAGAAAGGGGAUGUGGGCCAGGUGCGGUGGCUCACGCCUGUAAUCCCAGCACUUUGGGAGGCUGAGGCAGGCGGAUCACCUGAGGUCAGGAGUUCGAGACAAGUCUGGCCAACAUAGUGAAACCCCAUUUCUACAAAAAUACAAAAAAAAUUAGCCAGGCAUAAUGGUGGAUGCCUGUAAUCCCAGCUACUCAGGAGGCUGAGGCGGGAGAAUUGCUUGAACCUGGGAGGUGGAGGCUACAGUGAGCCGAGAUCAUGCCAUUGCACUCCAGCCUGGGUGAUAGAGCGAGACUCUGUCUCAAAAAAAAAAAAAAAAAAAAAAAAAAAAAAAAGGAGAUGUGUUACUUAGAAAUCUGGGUUUACAGGCCAGGCAUGAUGGCUCACGCCUGUAAUCCCAGCACUUUGGGAGGCCAAGGCGGGUGGAUCACUUGAGAUCAGGGGUUCAAGACCAGCCUGGCCAACAUGGUGAAACCCUGUCUGUACUAAAAAUACAAAAAAUUAGCUGGGCGUGGUGGCGGGCGCCUGUAAUCUCAGGUACUCGGGAGGCUGAGACAGGAGAAUACUUUGAACCUGGGGGGCAGAGGUUGCAGUUAGCCGAGAUUGCACCAUUACUCUCCAGCCUGGGCAACAGAGCAAAACUCCAUCUCAAAAAAAAAAAAAAGAAAUGUGGGUUUACAGAGGAGUGGAACCAAAUUUUAUUAUGGGUUAUACUUUGCAUAGAAUACUGUCUUCAGGAACUCUGAGAACACACUUUGUUCUAUUUCUUUUCUAAGCCACGGUGAGAGAAUUUUAAUCACGAUCAGCAAGGCUGAACUAUGCCCAUGUAGGCACAGGCCCAAGCACACAUAGUGCCACUCUGCUCUUCUGUUUGUCUCCUGGAAGUGGUACCUUAUUGCUUUCCUCUUUGGAUUGGUGAGGUUAUAAUAAUGCUUUCUGUAGGCCAGGCGCGGUGGCUCAUGCCUGUAAUCCCAGCACUUUGGGAGGCCGAGGUGGGUGGAUCACCUGAGGUCAGGAGUUCGAGACCAGCCUGACCAACAUGGUGAAACCAUGUCUCUUCUAAAAAUACAAAAUUAGCCAGGCAUGGUGGUGCAUGCCUGUAAUUCCAGCUACUCAGGAGACUGAGGCAGGAGAAUUGCUUGAACCUGGGAGGCUGAUAUUACAGUGAGCCGAGAUCACGCUAUUGCACUCCAGACUGGGCAAUAAGAGUGAAACUCCAUCUCAAAGAAUAAUAAUAAUAAUAGUAAUAAUAGUGCUUUGUGUAAAAGGUACAACCCUAUCUACAGGUGGAUAGUGUUUAAAAAAAAAAAAGUGAAAGGUAUAAUUCAUCUUAGGCCCAGGGCAUGGUAAGUAAGAGAGAAGUCUAGAGGUCUACAGGUUUUCCUUCCCACAUUCUAAUUGUCUUCUUAAAUGGUUUAAGUUUUUAUAACACAUAAUGAUGUGGAAAGUAAAGAGUCUACAUUAGAAUAUUUUUCUUGGGUGUUGAGGAGUAUAGGCGGAGUAGAGCUUGGGAGAGUAGCCAGGAAGAAAUAGCAGCAUUAUUCAAAGAAUCCAAAAGGUAGAAGCAAUCCUAGUGUCCAUCGACAGAUGAAUGGAUAAAUAAAAUGUUGUGUACACAUACAAUGAAAUAUUAGUCUGUAUUAAAAAAGAAAAUUCUGAGGCCGGGAGCGGUGGCUCACACCUGUAAUCCCAGCAUUUUGGGAGGCCAAGGUGGGUGAAUCAUGAGAUCAGAAGUUCGAGACCAGCCUGGCCAAUGUGGUGAAAUCCCAUCUCUACUAAAAAUACAAAAAUUAGCCUGGCAUGGUGGUGGAUACCUGUAAUCCCAGCUAGUCGGGAGGCUGAGGCAGGAGAAUUGCUUGAACCCAGGAGGCGGAGGUUGCAGUGAGCUGAGAUUGCGCCACUGCACUCUAGCUUGGGCGACAGAGCAAGACUCCAUCUCGAAAAAAAAAAGGAAAUUCUGGCAAAUGGUACAACAUGGAUGAAUCUUGAAGACAUUAUGCUGAGUGAAAUAAAGUGGAUAUAAAGGACAAAUAUUGUAUGAUUCCUCUUAUGUGAGGUUUCCAGAGUGGUCAAAUUUGUAGAGACAGAAAGUAGAACGGUGGUUGCCCAGGGCUGGGGGAUGGUGGUGGUGAUGGUAAUGGAGUUAUUGUUAAAAGGGUACAUUUUCCGCUAGUGAAGAUGCAGAAGUUAUGGGGAGAUGGAUGGUGGUGAUGCUUGCACAACAGUGUGAAAGUACUUAAUGCCACGGAACUGUACCUGUAGAAAAGGUUUAAAUGAUACAUUUUAUGUAUAUUUUACCACAAUAAAAAAAAAAGAAGCAGCCGGGCAUGGUGGCUUAUUCCUGUAAUCCCAACACUUUGGGAGGCCAAAGUAGGCAGAUUGCUUGAGGUCAGGAGUUUGAGACCAGCUUGGCUAACAUGGUGAAACCCUGUCUCUACUAAAAAUACAAAAAUUAGCUGGGUGUGGUGGCACAUACCUGUAGUCCCAGCUACUCAGGAGGCUGAGACAGGAAAAUUGCUUGAACCCGGGAGGCAGAGGUUUCAGUGACCUGAGAUCGCGCCACUGCACUCCAGCCUGGGUGACAGAGCAAGACUCCGUCUCCCAAAAAGAAAAAAAAAAAAGAAGCAAUAGCAUUGAUUGAAGUAAAGGUAAAGGUUUGUAGCCUGGGCAACAGAGCCUGGGCAACAGAACCUGGGCAACAGUAUCUACAAAAAAAAAAAAAAUUGAGCUGGGCAUGGUGGCACAUGCCUGUAUUCCUAGCUGCUCAGGAGGCUGAGGCAGGAGGAUCACUUGAGCCCAGAAGUUUGGGUCUGCAGUGAGCCAUGAUUGCACCACUGCACUCCAGUGACAGAGUGAGGCCCUAUCUCUUAAAAAAAAAAAAAAAAAAGCAUAAAAAAGGAAGGUAAAGGUUUGACUGAGAUCAUUCCUUUGGUUUUUCAUUAAACAAAUGUUUGAGCACCUACUACAUGCCAGGUACUAUUUUAGGCCCAGGAUACAGUGAUGAAUAAAUCAGGUAAGGCCCUUGCUUUCUUAGAACUUAUGAUCUAAUAAGAGAGACAGACUAUAGAGAAGACGGGUGAAUAAACAAGAUUUAUUGUGGUGACAAGGUCUGUGAAGGAAGUGAAUACAUGAGAUGAGAAAGGCAUAGGGAGAUGUCACUAUAGAAAGAGUGGUCAGUGAAAACCUCUCUGAGGAGUUGAAAUUUGAGCUGAAGGCCCAGGCACAGUGGCUUACACCUAUAAUCCCAGCACUUUGGGAGGCUGAGGCAGGAGGAUUGCUUGAGCCCAGGUGUUCAAGACCAGCUGUCUGGGCGCAGUGGCUCAUGCCUGUAAUCCCAGGGCUUUGGCAGGCUGAGGCAGGUAGAUCACAAGGUCAAGAGAUCGAGACCAUCCUGGCCAACAUGGUGAAACCCCAUCUCUACUAAAAAUACAAAAAUUAGCUGGGCGUGGUGGCACAUGCCUAUAAUCCCAGCUACUCGGGAGUCUGAGGCAGAAUUGCUUGAACCCGGGAGGCGGAGGUUACAGUGAACCGAGAUCAUGCCACUGCACUCCAGCCUGGGCGACAGAGCAAGACUCCAUCUCAAAAAAAAAAAAAAUUCAGGCCAGGCGCGAUGGCUCACGCCUGUAAUCCCAGCACUUUGGGAGGCCGAGGUGGUUAGAUCAUGCGGUUAGAUCAUGAGGUUAGGAGAUCGAGACCAUCCUGGCUAACACGGUGAAACCCUGUCUGUACUAAAAACACACACACAAAAAAUUAGCCAGGCGUGGUGGUGGGCGCCUGUAGUCCCAGCUACUCGGGAGGCUGAGGCAGGAGAAUGGCGUGAACCCAGGAGGCGGAGCUUGCCGUGAGCUGAGAUCCCACCACUGCACUCCAGCCUGGGCAACAGAGCAAGACUCUGUCUCAACAACAACAACAAAAAACAAUUUAUCUAGACAAAGACCUUGCACCUUUCACCAGCCUGGGCAACACAGUGAGACCCUAGCUCUACAAAAAUUUUUAAAAAUUAGCCAGGUGUGGUGUCUGUGGUCCCAACUACUCUGGAGGCUGAGGUGAGAGGAUCCUUUGAGCCUGGGAGGUUGAGGCUGUAGUGAGUCAUGAUUGUGCUACUGCACUCCAGCCUGGGAGACAGAGCAGGACCCUGUCUGAAAAAAAUAAAUAAAUAAAAUAAAAUAAACCAACCAAAUUAAACAGAGCAGAAAAAAAAAUACAUAUAUAUGAAGUCUCUCCUAGCUACUUCCUUUCUCUGGAAUUCUGAUAUAUACCUUACAAGGAGUAAAUUAGAUUUUAAAAUUACUUUUAUGUCAUCUUAGUGGACUCACCAUUUUAUUUUGGAGGGGAGUGAUAUUUAAACCUGUAGAUAUUAAUCCAUGUUCUUAUGCCUUUGUGCCUAAUAAUCGCUCUGCCUGGAAUGACCACCCCUUGUCUCAUUUCUGUUUGUCUUUCAAGGCCUUGUUCAAAUGUUACCUCUCCUUGAUAUUUCCCCAGCUGCACCAGAAAGCCACGUCUGCCAUACACUUUGUUCCCCCAGCAUUUUGGAUAUGUUGUAGUGCUUAGGAUGUACUCGAGAGUCGUGUGUCUUGCCCUCCUCUACUAGAUAGUGAGUUCCUAAGGACAGAGUCUAAAUCCAUGGAUCUUAAUAGCUCUAGAGCAGUGGAUUCGGGCCUUUUAGUAUUUGCAGCACUCUAUUUAAGACCCUUAAUCUUAGUGGCAUUCUUGAAGUGAUUCAAAACCUAAAAACCAAGCUAAAUUCAGUUGUGGGACAAGACAUUCACAUCCUCAGGCUGGCGAUUUGUCACGGCACCUAUAAAAUCACCCAGUGUUAUCACCCUAUUCUCUUGGUAGCCCUUCAGCAACAUGGCAGAAAUCUAAUGAUUUUGCUUUCUGAUUCCUAUCUCAUGGACCCAAGCAAAGUUCUCCUAUCUCCUAGUUUCUAGAAGGCUUAAAGAGAAAGAAACAUGAUAAAGCCAGGAGACCAUCUGAGCCAUCAUAUUUAUUUGAAACUCAAUUUCUUUACCUCCAGGACUCCCAAGUGGUAGAGAAUUACUUGAAAUUUGAGACAAUUUUGCCCAGGAGGCUCUAUUCCCAAAGCUGUGGUCAGCUCUCAUGGUGCCUGUGUGGUGCCUAUUGUUGGUUUUCCCUGAGUGGUACCUGGUAGAUUUGAUGUUUGUGUGAGGUGACCUAAUUUACAGAACCACGUAAGGAGUGUUUUGGGGGGGGGCGUUUAACAUUCUAGGUUAAGAAAAAGGACAUUUGGCUUUCUUUGUAUGAAGUUUUCUGAUUUGUUGGAAGAGGGACCAUACUUCAUCUAAUCUAAGAACUCAUCAAUUCUCAAUUCUUCAGUGUUACAACUUUUUAAAAGCCCUACAAGUAAUGGCAAUUGUUCUUGGAAAAUCGAUUAAUUGGCUGUCAGUUUUCUGUCUAGUGUCUUAUAUAUUUAGUUCCUUGAGAAGGGGCAACACACUACAGAAUUUUGACUAACUUUGUGUUUUUCCCUUACAGUUGCUUUUCGACUAUAUGAUUUGGAUAAAGAU